CUUCUUCCGCUCUGAGGCGCUACUGAGGCCGCGGAGCCGGACUGCGGUUGGGGCGGGAAGAGCCGGGGCCGUGGCUGACAUGGAGCAGGUGGGUCCCGGAGCGGUCGCUGGGAGCGGGUGGCGUGCGAGGGCCGUCUUCCGCCGGUCGAACCCGCUUCGCCGCCCGCUGUCCGUGCUGGGUUCCGUCCGACCCUUCCCACACCCGCUGCGUCUCAGGUUCCGCCCCCUUCCUCUGUCUGGCCUCGCGCCGCCCCGCGCGGGUUGGGGUCUCCAGCAAUGACUCUUGGCGACCCCGCCUAUCCUGGGGAGCCCGGGGAGGACGUUCGGGAUCUCCUUCCAAAGCCUCCGUCUUAACUGAGGGGAGAGGAGAGGCCCUGCUGCUGAGGCCGCGCCCUCCCCGCCCUGAGGUGGGGGCCCACCAGGAUGAGCAAGCUGCCCAGGGAGCUGACCCGAGACUUGGAGCGCAGCCUGCCUGCCGUGGCCUCCCUGGGCUCCUCACUGUCCCACAGCCAGAGCCUCUCCUCGCACCUCCUUCCGCCGCCUGAGAAGCGAAGGGCCAUCUCUGAUGUCCGCCGCACCUUCUGUCUCUUCGUCACCUUCGACCUGCUCUUCAUCUCCCUGCUCUGGAUCAUCGAACUGAAUACCAACACAGGCAUCCGUAAGAACUUGGAGCAGGAGAUCAUCCAGUACAACUUUAAAACUUCCUUCUUCGACAUCUUUGUCCUGGCCUUCUUCCGCUUCUCUGGACUGCUCCUAGGCUAUGCCGUGCUGCGGCUCCGGCACUGGUGGGUGAUUGCGGUCACGACGCUGGUGUCCAGUGCAUUCCUCAUUGUCAAGGUCAUCCUCUCUGAGCUGCUCAGCAAAGGGGCAUUUGGCUACCUGCUCCCCAUCGUCUCUUUUGUCCUCGCCUGGUUGGAGACCUGGUUCCUUGACUUCAAAGUCCUACCCCAGGAAGCUGAAGAGGAGCGAUGGUAUCUUGCCGCCCAGGUUGCUGUUGCCCGUGGACCCCUGCUGUUCUCCGGUGCUCUGUCCGAGGGACAGUUCUAUUCACCCCCAGAAUCCUUUGCAGGGUCUGACAAUGAAUCAGAUGAAGAAGUUGCUGGGAAGAAAAGUUUCUCUGCUCAGGAGCGGGAGUACAUCCGCCAGGGGAAGGAGGCCACGGCAGUGGUGGACCAGAUCUUGGCCCAGGAAGAGAACUGGAAGUUUGAGAAGAAUAAUGAAUAUGGGGACACCGUGUACACCAUUGAAGUUCCCUUUCACGGCAAGACGUUUAUCCUGAAGACCUUCCUGCCCUGUCCUGCGGAGCUCGUGUACCAGGAGGUGAUCCUGCAGCCCGAGAGGAUGGUGCUGUGGAACAAGACAGUGACUGCCUGCCAGAUCCUGCAGCGAGUGGAAGACAACACCCUCAUCUCCUAUGACGUGUCUGCAGGGGCUGCGGGCGGCGUGGUCUCCCCAAGGGACUUCGUGAAUGUCCGGCGCAUUGAGCGGCGCAGGGACCGAUACUUGUCAUCAGGGAUCGCCACCUCACACAGUGCCAAGCCCCCGACGCACAAAUAUGUCCGGGGAGAGAAUGGCCCUGGGGGCUUCAUCGUGCUCAAGUCGGCCAGUAACCCCCGUGUUUGCACCUUUGUCUGGAUUCUUAAUACAGAUCUCAAGGUGGGGUGCUGGGGGGCUGCCAGGGCCGCCUGCCCCGGUACCUCAUCCACCAGAGCCUCGCGGCCACCAUGUUUGAAUUUGCCUUUCACCUGCGACAGCGCAUCAGCGAGCUGGGGGCCCGGGCGUGACUGUGCCCCCUCCCACCCUGCGGGCCAGGGUCCUGUCGCCACCACUUCCAGAGCCAGAAAGGGUGCCAGUUGGGCUCGCACUGCCCACAUGGGACCUGGCCCCAGGCUGUCACCCUCCACCGAGCCACGCAGUGCCUGGAGUUGACUGACUGAGCAGGCUGUGGGGUGGAGCACUGGACUCCGGGGCCCCACUGGCUGGAGGAAGUGGGGUCUGGCCUGUUGAUGUUUACAUGGCGCCCUGCCUCCUGGAGGACCAGAUUGCUCUGCCCCACCUUGCCAGGGCAGGGUCUGGGCUGGGCACCUGACUUGGCUGGGGAGGACCAGGGCCCUGGGCAGGGCAGGGCAGCCUGUCACCCGUGUGAAGAUGAAGGGGCUCUUCAUCUGCCUGCGCUCUCGUCGGUUUUUUUAGGAUUAUUGAAAGAGUCUGGGACCCUUGUUGGGGAGUGGGUGGCAGGUGGGGGUGGGCUGCUGGCCAUGAAUCUCUGCCUCUCCCAGGCUGUCCCCCUCCUCCCAGGGCCUCCUGGGGGACCUUUGUAUUAAGCCAAUUAAAAACAUGAAUUUAAAAAAAAAAAAAAAUUCCAGCCCCUCCCACUGCCUUGCCUCUUGAGGGAAGAGAAAGGCAGGCAGCAGCUUGGAUGAAGAGGGAAGACCCCUCACACAGCCUCUCCUGGGCUCACAGGAGGGCGGAGCCCGGGGAGCCAGUUCCUGAAACAUGCCCCCCAUUCCCCCCCCGCCCACCCCCCACUCCCCGCUUUCCUGACCAGUUCAACUGAGCAGAUGACUGGUCAGAAAAAAAUGCCCCGCCCCCUGCCAGGCUUCAGCGGGGCAAGUUUAAAGUCUCUAGUCCAGGAAUGGAGGUGGGGGUAUGGGCACCUGGCAGUGCCCACAGCAAGCCUUGACUGUGUGGCCUGGAGAUGGGGCCUGAGCUUCAGGGUCACUGAGGCACCUCUGGGAUCCAGGCCACCUGGAGCCCCGGACCUCCCAGACUCCACUCACCCAUUCCCUCUCCCCGCACGGCACUCACACCAGGGGCGGCCUGGAGCCCGGAUCGCAGGGCGGGGCCAGGCCACUGCCUGCCUUCCUCCUCCCUCCCGGCUGGCCUGCCCCCUUGCCUGCCUGCAUGCAGGCUUCCAGCAGAGCCAGCUUCUUCAGAGCCAGGUGGAUCCUGUUUCGGUCCUGCCUAGGUGUGUGACCCUGGGCGAAUCUACCUCUCUCAGCUUCUGCUUCCCACUUUAUGAAAAUGGGACUGAUGUCACAGGGUUGUUAUGAGAUUAAAAGAUAUGAAGAACCGGG